ACUGGAGUUUGGUUCUCGAGGCGGCGGCAGCGAGCGGCGGCGGCUCCGGCGGCUCCUCCUCCUCCUUUGGUGGCGGCGGCGGCCCGGGACCGAGACCCGGCCCCGGCUCCCCUCUCCGCCACCCCGCGCGCCCCCAACCCCCCGGCGCCGCGGGGAACAUGCGGCUCCGGCUCCCGGAGGCCGGCGAGUGAGUGACCCCCGUCCCCCGCCUCAGCCCGCCCGCCCGCUGGCCCGGCCGCAACCCCCCGCCUCGCCCAGGCAAUGACAGCGGCUCCGGCGUCUCCGCAGCAGAUCAGGGACCGGCUGCUGCAGGCCAUCGACCCCCAGAGCAACAUCCGGAACAUGGUGGCGGUGCUGGAAGUCAUCUCCAGCCUGGAGAAAUACCCUAUUACCAAAGAGGCACUUGAGGAAACACGACUUGGGAAGCUCAUCAACGACGUCCGCAAGAAAACCAAGAACGAGGAGCUCGCCAAGCGGGCCAAGAAGCUGCUGCGGAGCUGGCAGAAGCUCAUCGAGCCGGCACACCAGCAUGAGGCGGCGCUGCGGGGGCUGGCGGGGGCCACCGGCUCUGCCAACGGGGGCGCACACAACUGCCGGCCGGAGGUGGGGGCGGCUGGCCCACCCAGGAGCAUCCAUGACCUGAAGAGCCGCAAUGACCUCCAGAGGCUGCCCGGGCAGCGGCUGGACAGGCUGGGCAGCCGCAAGCGCCGGGGUGACCAGCGUGACCUCGGCCACCCAGGGCCGCCACCCAAGGUCUCCAAAGCUAGCCACGACCCCCUGGUCCCCAACUCAUCCCCCCUCCCCACCAACGGGAUCAGUGGGAGUCCAGAGAGCUUCGCCAGCUCCCUGGAUGGCAGUGGGCAUGCAGGCCCAGAGGGCAGCCGCCUGGAGCGUGACGAGAAUGACAAGCACAGUGGCAAGAUCCCCGUCAACGCCGUGCGACCGCACACCAGCUCCCCGGGCCUGGGCAAGCCCCCUGGACCCUGCUUGCAGCCAAAGGCUUCGGUGCUGCAGCAGCUGGACAGGGUGGACGAGACUCCGGGGCCUCCCCAUCCCAAGGGACCCCCUCGCUGCUCUUUCAGUCCUCGGAACUCACGGCAUGAGGGCUCCUUUGCCCGGCAGCAGAGCUUGUAUGCACCCAAGGGCUCCGUGCCCAGCCCCUCACCGCGGCCCCAGGCACUCGAUGCCACACAGGUGCCGUCACCGCUUCCACUGGCACAGCCGUCCACACCCCCCGUACGGCGGCUCGAGCUGCUGCCCAGUGCGGAAAGCCCAGUGUGCUGGCUUGAGCAGCCUGAGAGCCACCAGCGGCUGGCGGGGCCGGGCUGCAAGGCAGGGCUGUCCCCAGCCGAGCCCCUCCUGUCCCGGGCAGGCUUUUCCCCAGACUCCUCCAAGGCGGACAGUGAUGCUGCCUCCUCAGGGGGCUCGGACAGUAAAAAGAAGAAGAGGUACCGACCUCGAGACUAUACGGUUAACUUGGACGGGCAGGUGGCUGAGGCGGGCGUCAAGCCUGUCCGGUUAAAAGAGCGGAAGCUCACCUUUGACCCCAUGACGAGACAGAUCAAACCUCUGACCCAGAAAGAGCCAGUGCGGGCAGACAGCCCUGUGCACAUGGAGCAGCAGUCCAGGACAGAGCUGGACAAGCAGGAGGCCAAGGCCAGCCUCCAGAGCCCCUUCGAACAGACGAACUGGAAGGAGCUGUCACGCAACGAGAUCAUCCAGUCCUACCUGAGCCGGCAGAGCAGCCUGCUCUCAUCAUCGGGCGCGCAGACCCCAGGGGCUCACCACUUCAUGUCUGAGUACCUGAAGCAGGAGGAGAGCACCCGGCAAGGGGCCAGGCAGCUGCAUGUGCUGGUGCCUCAAAGCCCGCCCACGGACCUCCCUGGUCUGACCCGGGAGGUCACACAGGACGAUCUCGACAGAAUCCAGGCCAGCCAGUGGCCGGGGGUGAACGGGUGUCAGGACACACAGGGUAACUGGUAUGACUGGACGCAGUGCAUAUCGCUCGAUCCGCACGGCGACGACGGGCGCUUGAACAUUCUGCCUUAUGUCUGCUUGGACUGACCGGCCUGUCAGCCACAAAGUGCAUUCCCAUCUUGCAGAAGCCGGGUGGGCGGGCAGGCAGGUGGGCAGGUGGCCGGGGCCCAGCUGCCUCCUGCGCUGGGAACUCGGGGAGUCCGGCCCAGGCGGGAGGGAGGGGGCGGGAGUCACGCGGUCUCUCUGCGCUCUUCCCUCAAAACUCUUUUUGUGAAAUGCUGCUACCAGUUUACUAACAAAAUUGCGAAGAAGGACCGCGUGGAAGGAAGGACGGCAAAGUGAGUUCAGAACUCUAUAGCAAACCAGCUAUAAAAAGCGUUAGUCCCUCACCCCCAAAGAGGUGCGGACACUUUCCAGCACCUGAAAGCUGGGGCCUCAGUUGCAGGCAGGCACAGAAAACCUGUGGGAGAGGUCACCUUUAACACAGCAACAGAAGCACGCAUCUCAUCUCUCUUGCAUUUUCUGUUCUUUAAUUUGGCCCUGAGUGUCUUGAGACAGUGGGCCAUGCCACUGCCUCUGUUUGCUCCCUACCCAGCCACUGUCAGGCCAGUGUUGUCUGUCAUGUGCCAGAAGCUUCUCAGCUGUGGUGAGCCACUGGCAUUGGGCAGGCGGGCCAGCUGGCCAGCCAGUGUGACCCACACUCCAUGGGCAGCCACCUGUUUAUAUCUGGUUUCAGUUAUAACCCAGUUUUUAAAGAAAUGCUGCAAAAAUUUAAGUUUUCUCAUGUUUAUUUUAAACAAUUCCUCUUCCAUCAGACCACCAGACAAAAAAACCUUUCCUUUCUUCCUCCCUUUUCUUUUUUCCCUUCCUGUACACAUCUAGAAAACUUCACCUUUCUAGAGUCCCCCCAAAACAACACAAAAGUUAUUGUGGGUGCUACUGGUUUUAUGCUGUACUGUGGGGCGAGGGGGAAGACCUGUCUGUACGCUGGAAACACUCAUAACCAUUCCUUUAGAUUCGUUUGCCUUAUGGUUAUUUGUCAUAAACGCGAUUUGCAAAAACAAGGAGCCUUAGUGAAUGUACAGUACCUAGACUUCUGUGUUCUCAGGACGCAGAAGGGAGCAACUUUGCUAUUUGGUCCAGUAAGUGGACACCUUGUGAUAUAAAUGUGGAAAUAAAAAAAAAAAAAAAACCA